GAGCCUUGCAAACAAGUGUCUGUGCUGUGUCCCCGCGGCCCUCCUCGCGCCGGGGCCGCUUCCUCCGGGUAGGAGGGAGCAAGGGAGCCCUCGCCGCGCGGCCCGCGAGCCGCCGCCGCCCUCGGCCCGCGCAUCCCCGCGCGGGGGCCGCGGAUUCGACUAGGCUGCCAGGCGCAGCGACACCGGGUCGCGGUGCGAGCGGCGCCCCGGCUCUCGCCGAGAGGCUCCUGACAGAAAAACGUGCGUGGUUGUCCCCACCCCUGGGAGGGGUUGCCGGUGCCGCGCGCGGCCGCCCAGUCGCCAGCGCUCUCUCCUGGGAGGAUCCGCUGCCGGAGGAAGGAGUGGACCCAACCUGGCCGCGCCGCAGAAGUGGCUCCCGAGGAAGCCGGCGCCGGGGCCGCCGCCUCGUGUCCCCUCGGGGCGCAGUGCUCGGGGGUCGGCGGGCCAGAGCCGAGGCGCGGCCGGGGAGCCGGGGGCUGCGGGGCCGAGCGGGCAGCCGCGCGAGGGGGCGGGCGCUCGGCGACCCGGGGGCCGGCCGGGCUGAGCCCCGCGCCCCGGGACGCGGGCUGGAAGCGACGGAGGAGUGCUGCCGCGGGCUGCGGACCAGCGCCGUCCCCUCACGGAGCGGGGAUUCUGCUAUGACAGUUGGGCUCCCCGGAGGGUUAACCUGGGUGUCCUCGGCAAAGUUGUCGCCGAGCCGGGAGCCCGUGUAGGGGCCGCGGCGCCGCGGCUCGGGGGGCGGCCGGGCGGCCGGCGGCGGUCGUGGCUCGGCGGGGCCCGCGCGGCCGGGGGGCUCCUGGGGGUGUGCGCCCCCAGCCGGCUGCCCUCGUGGAUGCCUCCCGGCGGCGGCGGGCCCAUGAAAGACUGCGAGUACAGCCAGAUCAGCACCCACAGCUCCUCCCCCAUGGAGUCGCCCCACAAGAAGAAGAAAAUCGCGGCCCGGAGGAAAUGGGAGGUGUUCCCGGGAAGAAACAAGUUCUUCUGUAACGGGAGGAUCAUGAUGGCCCGGCAGACGGGCGUCUUCUACCUGACGCUCGUCCUCAUCCUGGUCACUAGCGGACUCUUCUUCGCCUUCGACUGUCCGUACCUGGCGGUGAAAAUCACCCCUGCCAUCCCUGCAGUCGCUGGCAUCCUGUUCUUCUUUGUGAUGGGGACCCUGCUCCGCACCAGCUUCAGCGACCCCGGAGUCCUCCCACGAGCCACGCCUGAUGAAGCCGCCGAUCUGGAAAGGCAAAUAGAUAUCGCAAACGGCACCAGUUCAGGGGGGUACCGCCCGCCUCCCAGAACCAAAGAAGUCAUCAUCAAUGGCCAGACCGUGAAACUUAAAUACUGUUUCACCUGCAAGAUUUUCCGGCCCCCUCGCGCCUCCCAUUGCAGCCUUUGUGAUAACUGCGUAGAACGGUUUGAUCACCACUGUCCCUGGGUAGGCAACUGUGUGGGGAAAAGAAACUACAGAUUUUUUUAUAUGUUUAUUUUAUCUCUGUCUUUUCUGACAGUCUUUAUAUUUGCAUUCGUUAUCACCCACGUCAUUCUUCGUUCACAGCAAACAGGAUUCCUAAAUGCCCUUAAGGACAGUCCUGCAAGCGUCCUGGAGGCUGUGGUGUGCUUCUUCUCUGUCUGGUCCAUCGUUGGCCUCUCAGGAUUCCACACCUACUUGAUCAGCUCCAACCAGACAACAAAUGAGGACAUUAAAGGAUCCUGGUCAAAUAAAAGAGGUAAAGAAAAUUACAAUCCCUACAGCUACGGAAAUAUCUUUACCAACUGCUGUGUUGCCCUGUGUGGGCCCAUCUCACCAAGCCUGAUCGACAGAAGAGGGUACAUCCAGCCCGACACGCCGCAGCCAGCAGCACCCUCCAAUGGCAUCACCAUGUACGGGGCCACGCAGUCACAGAGUGACAUGUGCGACCAAGACCAGUGCAUUCAGAGCACCAAAUUCGUUUUGCAGGCUGCAGCCACGCCCCUGCUGCAGAGCGAGCCCAGCCUCACCAGCGACGAGCUGCACCUGCCCGGGAAGCCUGGCCUGGGCACGCCCUGCGCCAGCCUCACACUGGGCCCGCCCACACCGCCCGCCUCCAUGCCCAACCUCGCCGAGGCCACGCUCGCGGACGUGAUGCCCCGGAAAGAUGAGCACAUGGGCCACCAGUUCCUGACGCCCGAUGAGGCGCCCUCGCCCCCCAGGCUACUGGCGGCGGGCAGCCCCCUGGCGCACAGCCGCACCAUGCACGUGCUGGGCCUGGCCAGCCAGGACUCCCUGCAUGAGGACUCUGUGCGCGGCCUGGUGAAGCUCAGCUCCGUGUGACCCACAUGGCCCCAGGCCGGGGGACACCAGAGGCUCCUCCAUGGGCAGCAGGAGUGAGCGGAGGGGUGUGUCCCACAGCGACUUUCCCAGCCAAUGCCACGGUGGAGAUGACAGCCCCAGGUCUGGGGUACAGAGACCACUUAGGAUGGCACAGGGUGGCUGGCCCCGGAUGCUGAGAGCUUGGUUUCAUUUGAAUUUUCUUCCCCAACCUGAGUGCUUUGACAACAAUGGAAAUAGAGAAGUGGCUGCUUUCUUUUGGUGACCCUCCAGGGGUGGAAUCGGAGUGUGUCUGCCCGCCCUUGUGACAGACACACGGAAGGCUUCUGACGCUUGUGGCCAGACUGCAAUUGCACUUAUGUGUUAUGCUACUAAUAUUUGAAACAGACCUGCCAUUCCAUUUGUUAAUUAAAAAAAAAAAAAAUCCUAAAGGGAAAAAACCGACCAGGUGUGGAUCUGCAUGCCACGCUGCCGUCUGUGUUACAGUGGUGUUGCUAUUUCCAAGGAAGUGCUGCUUUCUUUUUCUUUUUUUAAUUUUGUGAAUUUUCAAGUGCUGUUUUGUUGGAAGACAGUGCAACGAACUGAGACUAAUGGACAGUGUCAUCACUCAGCUUACUGGGCUGAGGCGUCUGUGGAGAGGUGGCACCGGGGCUGCAGAGGGCGGCUGGGGUUCCGUCGUGUCGGGUGUCACUUCACCUUCUGUUUGGCCGCUCGAUGAGGUCUCGUGUUGAGAUAUUGUGUGCCACAACCCCCACAGUCUUCACCUCCGUGUGUGAUGAAACUUCCCGUGGACAGCCAAUAAAAUGACGUCCUCUGUUAUUUUGGAUCUGCGUACGGUUAUCCUUAAUAGCAUAAAUGAAAACAAAGUCAUCCAGAUGGGGAGAGUUUUUCUUGAAAUGUCCCUAGCGAGGAAUGGUCCCCAGACAACCAAAAGUCAAAUCUUUGAACUGGGAGAUAUUUAUAGAAUAAUUUCUUAGAUAAGAGGCAAGUUUUCCAUCAUUUAUUUUCUUUAAUUAUCUCUUUUUGACACCAUCUUAGUGGAAUUUGCUCUACGUUUGCAGUUUGCCGUGCAACAGUUGAUCGGAAGUAGGGAGAGGGGAGGGGACGCUCAGGGAGAAGGUUCUGUCGGGCGUCUUCUGGGCUUCCUUCUGUGUUAACGUGUCACUCAAUCCCAGAAGUGCAACUUGAGGUCCUAGUAAAGGUAUCAGAAAAUGAGGAGGAGAAAUCGGCUUACAGUCUAAGCUGAGAUCAUGUAGGUCAUCAUCCUUCCUAGACACUGAUCAGAAUGAAAUUAAGAAAAUGACCACUUUGUUCACUUUCAUUGGUCACCUAGAAGGGAACGAACUGGCUCUGGACUUAGGGAGUGUGUCACUAUGGGGGCAGCCACAGGGGACACAGCAACUCCUCUCCUGGCUUCUUUCCAGACCAUAAAUCUAACAGCUAAAGCUACUCAAGUUCAAAGCCAUGGCCUUGCUCCUUAUAACCAUAUGAAAGACAAGACACAUUGACCAAUGAUACAAGUAACCCAAGUGAUUUGCAUUUAUGGAAAAAGGCUAUUACUCCUGAGAAAGAGUUGCCAUUUUAUAUAAAAGAAAAGAAGAUAGGAAAAAGAAAAGCACACAAGUUUUAUUUGGAAUGAAGGCAAUUCACAGGUCACAAAAUAAUUCAUGCUGAAAGGGCCUGCAGAGUUCUUGCACUGUGAUGUCUUCGAGCCAUCUUUAUUGUCAUGCUGCAUGCACGUAUAGAAAAUGGAAUAGGUCCAUUCUAUGUAGCCAUUUUUGAUUUUCUGAACCACCUAACUACUUGUACCCACCUGCAAUGUGUAAUUCAUGGGGCAGUGCCCUCCUUACACAACCGCACACGCUCACAGGCACCAACUCACAGGGAUUCUCCUUGUCCACGCUACCUGUGAGCCCAAAGUGACAGCCCCACAAAGGAGCUUCCACAACUUCCCAAACCGUCUCUGCUCCUUGCUUUCUUCCACCUGCUCCCCAGAGGCCCCAGGAAGGAGUUGGCCCUGAUGAGAACGGUGCUCCAUGGGUGACCGCGAAUCCGGCUUAGCCCUCACUCCGGUCCCACGUGUGGCCCAGUCCAUUCUCAGCUCAUUCCCCUGGAAAGCAAGAUCAUGGUCUUCAGAGGCCUCCCGCUUCUAACAUUUCCUAACUCAGUGGUUGCCACUCUCCUGUGACCAGCCCUUCUUCCCACCUCACUGUGAAAAAUUCCCAGAAGCCAGGAUCACGACUCACUUGUCUUCACAUAAUGGAUAUUUACUUAAUAUUUAUUAUCAAUUUCCCCACCUCCAACCCUGUCCCUGGCACACACUUGGCAUCAUUUAUCCAAUAGGGGACUGGGAAUUUUGGUGAAGUGAAUCAAGGCUAUUCAGGGUCAAGAGAGAGAUUAACUUGAAUGGGCCAAUUUGCUAGAUAAUUAAUGUCUUAAAAACCAAAACCAGAGAGAAGCCCACAGCCCUGUCCUCUGUGGCUUGAAAAAGAAACCCAGCAUCAGAGGAAUGAGCGAUGAUGCCCCCUGGGGCGCCCACUUCUGUUUGUCAGGAGGGAUGGUCGGAGGGGCAGCUCACCUGGCGAGGUGAUGGCUCUGCAUUUCCCACGAACAUAUAUGUGACAUGUACAUAAAUAUAAAUACUUAUGUUUAUAAAUGUUGAAUGGUUCCUUCUAGCUGUGGCUGAGUAGACGUUGGUGUUUCUAACUUCUUUCAGUGUGUUAGAGAUUGAUUACAUGCUAGCUAUAAAAAGUAAAAUAAAUAUUUUACCAUGCUAUUAAAGCUUGGACCAUUAUCAAACACACACAAACACACACUCAUUCUGCUGUUUAAAAAUUCAUCUGCGUUCGUUCUCCCAGGAGUGCUCCAGGGAACCACAGGCUUCCCGGCACUUGAAGGCUGAACUGAGCGUGAGUGCCCUGGUCCCCAGGAAGCAGGCGGAUGCUGCAGGAAGGUGGCAGACAGCCUGCAUCCAGGAGGGCCCCAGGAAGUGGGGAUGCUGCAGGAAGGCGGCACAAAGCCUGCAUCCGGGAGGGCCCCAGGAAGCAGGGGGAUGCUGCAGGAAGGUGGCAGACAGACUGCAUCCAGGAGGGCACAGUGACCUGUCACUCCGUUCUGCAGAAAUUGGCCCAGCAGUUGCGUUAUGCCCAACCAAAAGAUGCUCGUUCCAGCUUUCAAAUGUGAUGAUUUCAGCCUGUGAGGACAAUGCCAUGUCCCCACCCUAAGCCAGCAAAAUGCGAAAUCUCUGUUCUGGCCCAGAAUGGCACAAGGGAGGAGUCUUUGCAGAGUUCCACGCCACCCCCCAGCUUACUGCGGCCUUCACCGGCUCUGUCUAGGAUUGCCAGCUGUGGUUCCAAGUGAGGAGCAAACCCAUUUUAUGAGCCAUGUUCCUGCGGAGACCUGAUGGGCCAGGCCUUCUGUGGCUUUGAAAACCCCUAAGCUCUUCACCUCCUGGGCCUAGGCCUUCUUGUCUGACUCAACAGCAAGAAAAAUGAACUUGCCAAAAUUGGCAGUAGGUGUCCUUGACACAGGGGCUUCUGAUGGCAUCGCCCAGAAAAUGCUGGAACCAGAACUGGUCAGAGACUUUGAAGGGCACAGCCUGGCGGGCUACUCCCCAAGGGUCUCAGGUCUCUGCCCACCUGACUACCCUGCAGCAAACGCUUCUCUGUAACCUGACUUCUCCCUUCAGACCUCAGCCUACAACCAUCCUCUUCAUGCCAGGAACCAACUGCUUCUCAGCCUCGGCUUAGGGUCUUAAGUUCACCAGAAGGGAUCGGGGUUUGCGUUGAUAUUAUAAGGAAUCUUCCCAGAAGGAGCUGCCCUUCAUCCAUCCACAAGAAUACAUUGAGUUCAUUUAGUUCUUGACCAGGUAAGAAAAGAAUAAAGGAGAACAAAUAUUAAAUACUCUUUUCUAAUUGAUGCCUUACUACUGUUUUGAAGCUGAGCCGAAAUCAAAUUGAUGUUUACAUUUUCUAUCAAGUACACAUGAGCUGUGGGAGUCUAGCAUAUUCUUGUCCAAAAGAGAGAGACUUUCAAAUGAAUUCCUAUUCCUCUUGGUCCCCUCCACCUAUUUUGGAGGUCUGCAUGUGGAGUUGUAUGCUAUUUUCCAAGGUACCUCAUUUAAAAAAAAAAAAAAAAAAAAACUGCCUCUCAUUUGUUCCCUUAAAACGUCUCUCUCUCUCAUAAAACUAAGUUAUCAUUGAAAUAUUAAACGAUCUGAAGCGUCUUUUUUUUUUUCAAAUAAAUGUCAAAGAUGGUAAUAGUUUGUAAAUCAGUAAAUCCUCUGUCCAUCUGCCCAUUGUCCAUGGUCCUGAUAAUAGAGCCAAGAUGGAUUUUCACAUGUAAGGUGUUAGUCCAUUAAUCCAGCCAUUAAAAGUAGUUGGGAGAUUGAAGAUUAGAUGGUUUCUGGAGCAACCGAAUUUGCAGCUGCCACAAAACUAGAUAAAUAGCCACAACUGGAGUUAUUUUUUGAUCUCAUAAACCCCAGGAAUUACACACAGAAUGGAUUGAAAAGCAGACAAGCAUCUUGUGCUAUUGCAGAGACUUUUCUACCCAGGAAGUGUUGAAUUUUUAAAAGAAACUUGAUAUUGGUGAUAAAGGUAUGAAUGAACAACUCUCUUACUUGCCCUCGAUGUUUCAAGAUGCCUGGUGAAACCGAGAGGCCACAUGGCAUGUCCAAGGAGACAUGCUUUCUGGGUUCUAUAUGAAUAGAGAUGGUUUUAGCCUGCAAUUAAAAAAAAAAAAAAAAACGGUUGAAGCCUUGCUAACUUUUUCCCAGAGCAUUCUGGGUUGAUAUUUCACAGUCAAACGUUUUGGCAUGGAAAAAAAAAAAAGCAUUUUAAACUCUUAGUGAAUUCAAAGCUCUAAAUCCAAACAAUGGUGAACACAUGUACAUAACAUUUCAUGUUUUCAGAGAUACGUAUGCUUAUUUAAGUGCCUUUCAUGUUUUAAUCAAUGUUUGCAGAAUUUAUCUUAAACCUGAGAUGAAUUAAAAAAUUUUUCUCCUUCAAUAAAAACUGCUAAUGGCAUAAAAUGUAAA